ACUCGUUUCCAAGGCGACGGCCCUGCUGCCUCUCCAGCCAAGUGGCUGGAGUCGGGAGGCUGGAAAGAGACUCCGAGAAAGUACCAGCGGAAGGCGGCCGCCGCUACGGCGAUUCGCAGGGAGUAGCAGACGAAGACGGUGGCCGCCGCACUAGCCACCACGUGUGGAGGAUAAACGGUCUACACGGCCAUUCCGGCGCCGAGUCUAGGGAAAGAGUUAGCGACGACGGGGAAAGAAAAUGUGAAGAGAGCGACCGCCGCUCCAGGGUCGCUGCAGGAAGCCUAAGUGCAGACGCCGGCUUCUCCCGCAGUGACUUGAGAAGGGUCAGUGAAAACCUCGGCCACUGCCGCAGCGUCUCUAGGGAGAGAGUUAGGGGAGAUAGUGGCCACAGUCACAGCUGCUCUUGGGAGAGAGUUAGGGGAGACAGCACCUUCUGCAGCAGCGACGUGAAUUUUAGUGAAGUUGGAGGCCACCAAACUACCGACUCCAGGGGAACAGCCAGAGAAGACCGAGGCCUCCGCCUCAGUGGUCCUUGGGAGGGAGUCAGUGACAUUCGGGACCCGCGAACUAGUGACUUCGGGGAUAGAGUCAGUGACGAUCGCAGUCGCCGCUUCAGUGGCUCCUGGGAGGGAGGGAGUGUCGAAGGCGGCCACAGCGUUGGUAGUUCUUGGGAGGAAGUAAGUGGAGACCGCGGCUACGCAGCCAGCGACUCCUCUGGUGUGAGCGGCAGUGAAGACGCCAGCUACCGCUUCAGUGGCUUUUGGGAGAGAGAAAGUGAAGACGAAGGUUUCCGCUGCAGCUUCUGGGAGAGAGCAAGAGAGGACCUUGGGCCCCGUCCUAGUGACGACGGAGAAGAGGGCCGCUGCCGCUGCAGUGGCUCGUGGGUGAGAGCAAGUGAAGACCGCCGCAGCAUCAGGGGCCUGGACUCAACUCCUCCCCAGAGUCGGAGGUGUUGCGCCAUGCCCGGGGUGGCCAAUUCAGGCCCCUCCACUUCCUCUAGGGAGACUGCAAACCCCUGUUCCAGGAAGAAGGUGCAUUUUGGCAGCAUACAUGAUGCAGUACGAGCUGGAGAUGUAAAGCAGCUUUCAGAAAUAGUGGUACGUGGAGCCAGCAUUAAUGAACUUGAUGUUCUCCAUAAGUUUACCCCUUUACAUUGGGCAGCACAUUCUGGAAGUUUGGAGUGUCUUCAUUGGCUGCUCUGGCAUGGAGCUGAUAUCACACACGUAACAACGAGAGGUUGGACAGCAUCUCACAUAGCUGCAAUCAGGGGUCAGGAUGCUUGUGUACAGGCUCUUAUAAUGAAUGGAGCAAAUCUGACAGCCCAGGAUGACCGGGGAUGCACUCCUUUACAUCUUGCUGCAACUCAUGGACAUUCUUUCACUUUACAAAUAAUGCUCCGAAGUGGAGUGGAUCCCAGUGUGACUGAUAAGAGAGAAUGGAGACCUGUGCAUUAUGCAGCUUUUCAUGGGCGGCUUGGCUGCUUGCAACUUCUUGUUAAAUGGGGUUGUAGCAUAGAAGAUGUGGACUACAAUGGAAACCUUCCAGAACCUCCUUAGAUCCCUGUGGAGCCUCUGAUUCCUUGGCUUGGCAUGCUGGACUUACAUAAUUUGGCACCUACCUACCUGCAUGGCCUCAUCUUUCUAUAUCUUUACACUACUGUCCAGGAUCAUUUUGUUUUUUUCUGAAGGUCGUCUUUCAGUGUUCAUUUAGUGAAGUCUUUUGGUAUGAACUCUUUCAAUUUUUGUGUAUCUGAAAAUUUAUUUUGUUCUCAUUCUUUUUACUUUGUAUUUUGUAAGUUUUUUUUUUUAAAGUAAAAUUUAAAUUGAAGUCUCAAAAAACAAAAAGCCCCUCUCUCGGCGCUGCCUACGGAGGUGGCAGCCAUCUCCUCCUCAGCAUCAUGGCCACCCUCAGACCCCUUGUGAAGCCCAGGAUCAUCAAAAAGAGAACUAAGAAGUUCUUCCGGCACCAGACUGACUGAUAUGUCAAAAUUAAGUGUAACUGGCAGAAACCCAGAGGUAUUGACAACAGGGUUCGUAGAAGGUUCAAGGACCAAUCUUGAUGCCCAACAUUGGUUGUGGGAGCGACAAAAAAAACAAAGCACAUGCUGCCUACUGACUUCUGGAAGUUCCUGGUCCACAACAUCAAGGAGCUGGAAGUGCUGCUGAUGUGCAACAGAUCUUACUGUGCUGAGAUGUUUCCUCCAAGAACUGCAAAGCCAUCGUGGAAAGAGCUGCCCAGCUGUCCAUCGGAGUCACACCAACCCCAACGCCAGGCUGCGCAGUGAAGAAAAUGAAUAGACAGCUCAUGUGCAUGUUUUGUGUUUAAAUAAAACUGUAAAAACUGCAAAGAAAAACCAAAAAACAACAACAAAAAAUUAUUUUGUGUUAGGCUUCCUUCGCUUUUUCAGACUGCUUUCAAUUUCCAUUUUCACAUAUGGUAUUAUUAGUUUUUUUUUUUAGUUUUAGUCUUUCUGAUGGAUGUAUCUCAUUGCAGUUUCAAAUUUACAUUUUUCCUGAUGACUAAAGAUGUUGAACAUCAUUUCGUACGUUUAAAGGCUAUUUGGUUUUUUUGUGUGUGUGAUGUACUAGUUCAAAUCUUUUGCCUAUUGGCUGUUAGAGUGUGUCUUUUUCUUAUUGAAUCAUAGGAGUUCUUUAUAUAUUCUAGAUACAAGCCCUUUGUCAGUUACGUUUAUUACCAAUAUCUUUUCAUGCAAAUAUCUUUCUAAUCUUUCUACUUCAUGGCUUGCUCUUUCAUUCUUUGGUAUUUUUUGAUAAAUGAGGUUUUAAUUAUUUUUUUUUUUUGAAAUAGAGUCUUGCUCUGUCGCACAGGCUGGAGUGCAGUGGUGCAGUCUCGGCUUGCUGCAACCUCUGCCUCCCGGAUUCAAGCGAUUCUUCUGCCUCAGCCUCCCGAGUAGCUGGGAUUACAGGUGUGCACCACCACGCUUGGCUAAUUUUUGUAUUUUUAGUAGAAACAGAAUUUUAGCAUGUUGGCCACGCUGGUCUUGAACUCCUGACCUUGUGAUCCACCCACCUCGGCCUCCCAAAGUGCUGGGAUUACAGGUGUGAGCCACCGCGCUUGGCCAGAGGUUUUAAUUUUAACGUAGUCCAUUUUAAUAAUCUCUUCCUUUGUAGUUAGUCCUUUCUGUACUUUCCCUAUUUUGUGAUCAUGAAGACAUUCCUUUAUGUUAUCUGUUAGAAAUUUUAUUUAUCUUUCAUAUUUAUAUUCCCAAUCCUCCUAGAACUGACUUUUCCGUGUGUAAUACAAGGUAGGGGUCAGUUUUAUUUUUGUAUUGUCCUUUAUCAAAUAUACUUGAUCAUUUUUGUUGGUCUUGUCUGGUCAUUAAAAAAUCCAAUUGUUUCUUUAAACAUGUAUGAUUAUUUUAUUUAUAACCAGGUAGAGUAUUUAUAAUAAUAUAGAUGUUAAGAAAGAAUGUGGCCUUAGGUCUAGACUGCUUGUGUUCAAAUCGCUCUCAUAAAAUUAUUUUUUAUUGAUAAAUGUACAUAUUUUUGGUGUACAUGUGAUAAUUUGAUACAUUCAUUUGUAUCAAAUUUGAUAAUGUAUAAAGAUCAAAUCAAGGUAAUUGGGGUAGCCAUCCCUUAAAUAUUUCUUUUAUACUAGGAACAUUUGAAUUAUUUUUUUCUAGUUAUUUUUAAAUACACAAUAGAUUAUGGUUAACUAUAAUCACCCUACUGAUCUGUCAAACACUAGAUCUUAUUUCUUCUACUCAAUUGUAUAUUUAUACCCAUUAAUCAACUUCUGUUCUUGCUCUCUCCGUGCUACCCUUCUGGCCUUUGGUAAUCGCCAAUCAAUCUACUCUCUAUCUUCAUGAGACCAGCGUAUUUUAGCUCCCACAUAUGAAUGAAAACAUAUAAUAUUUGUCUUUCUGUGCUUGACUUAUUUUACUUAACAUAAUGACCUCCAAUUCCAUCCAUCUUGUGGCACUGACAGUAUUUCAUUCAUUUUUGUGUGAAUUAUAUUUCGUUGUGAAUAUACAUUACAUUUUCUUUAUCCAUUCAUCACUGAUGUGCACUUAGGUUGAUUCCAUAUUUUGGCUAUUGUGAAUAGUGUGUUAAUAAACAUGAGAGUGCAGUUA